ACAGAUUGCUGGCUUCCUGGGUAGUAAUAAAUAUUUACUCAGCAAUCUCGAGUGAGUGUCCAUGGGGUGCUGUCAAGGAGACCUGGUGCCUGUCCUUGUGGAGUUCCUGUUUAGGCAGGCAAAGAACUCGAAGCAGUCAUCCCCCGAGUGUGCUGCCUGGGAGGAGCGGGUCUUGGGCCCAUAGUCCUGGGAGGCCUCUUGGUGGGUCCUUUCUGAAGACUGACAGCAGCAGCUCCUGCAGUUCUUCUGUAGAACGGGUCCUUAAAGGUUUUUGUUUUUUUUUUGAAAUGACGGCACCUGUGUUUUUUUCUUUACCUUAACACCUGAGAGUUCCUAAGAACACAAGUUAUAAAAUGCUGACCUAACCCCUUCAGAAACUGUGAAAGGGAAUCCUGAAACUUUGGCAGUUAAUAGAUUGUAUGGGCUUUCUCCGCCUUGCCCUGCUCUCUCUCCUGGGGUAGCUCACUCCCUUUCUCUUCAGUGAUGCCAUUGCCAGCUGAGCCAGCCAGCACGUUAACUCCUCUAUAACCGAUGGUCUGUAUCUCGUAGCUUAGCACUGGAACUCACCCAAGGCCUGGGGAUUCAGGGGCGAACAUGGACCCUGCCCUGGUCCAGCAGGUCAUUAUAGCCAUGGUCACCAUGCUUAUGGUGGCGAGGGUUCAGAUGGAGGUACAUGCUCAUUGUAGAAUUAUUAGAAAAAGGUAAUGAGCAAAAAGAAAAUGGAUAUUAACUCUUAGUAUUUUGGUAUGUAUGUUCUGAGACUUUUUUUCUUUAUGCAUACAUAAUACGUGUGUGUAUUUUAAGUUAAUAUAACGUUAUGUGUUGUUUAUACUUGUUUUUUUCACUCAAUAUAUUGUAAAGAUUUUCCACAAACAAUAAAUGCAUUUCCAGACUCUCAGUGUUAGUGAGUGGAUAAUAUUCCAUAGUAUUAAUGUGCCGUAAGUUAUUUAUACAUUCUGCUGCUGGGCUUAGGUUAUUGCUUACUUAUCGUUAUAAACAACAAUAUUAGAAUACUUUUCUAGCUCAAAUGUUGUGAGCAUCCUUAAUUAUUUCAGGAUACCUUCCCUAAAGGAAAAUUGCUUGGUAACAGAUUUUGUGCAUUUUUUGGGCUUUUGCUAGUUACGAGGCUGGUAGAGGCAAGGGUUGACUUGUGAUCAGCAGUGUGACUUGUGACAGCAGUAGCCGUUGUGGUGUCUCGCUGAGGCUGCAGCCGGGAGCCCCUUGUUCCACAUGUGCCUCCAGCCCCUGCAGUCUGCGCGCCUGGGGGGAUCACGCCGCUCUCCAGAUUGGCCCACCAUCCCUGACUUCAUUCGUUGUUUUGGGCUCUCCUUUUCUGAGUUAAUGAUUUAGGCUUGAUGUGAACUUCUGAAGUGUAGUUCUUUUUUACUUAAAAAAAAUUGAUGAUGAUAUAGAAACAGGAUCUAAUAGAGAUAGGACAUUUCAUGACUGUGUAUCUGAUUGACCUCUGAAAACAGUUACUGUUUUGGUGGUUGGCACUUGUUAAGUUUCCAUUUCCAUUCACCCCUGUAGGCGCACAGGAGAAUUCGCGUCUGGUCGGGAAUAAAUGUUGGUAAUUAUAAUCCUUGAGAAUGCCUUAAGGAUAAACUACCUAACUCAUAGGUUCUAGCAAGCUCCUACUGUGGAUAAAUACAAGUUAGUCCUCUGGGGGACCUUUGGAGUGAGCGGCUCUGGUCCCUUUGUCUUUGAGGGAAGAAAGUGUGCAGUGGGGUGGAUUGAAUGGAAUUAAAGCCAGCCACCAAGUUAUAAGUUUUCUUCUUGGUUCUGGUUGUUCACAUGGUGGAACAUGUAGAGUGUAUGCUGCUUCACUGUUUUGUCCACUGAUUUAUAAUUCCAUGAAUUUAGCCAUGCCUCCAAAGGAUAUGCUGGGGCACGGAAAAAAGGAACUUAGAGUCAGUUCAUUUUGCUACUUUUUGGUAAUUCAAGUAAAAUAUUUACUAAGGAGAACUGGUGAAGCUCAUAGAAUCAAUGUUUUAAAAUUAUUUCUGAGUUCAGAUUUAUUAAUCAUCUUUCUAGAUUACUAUUACCAAGGCUAAAGAAAUUUACCAUUUCCAGCCUAUCAGAUAAAUACGUUGCCUUGUCCAAAUCUGUUGGGAACUUUGUGUAAUUUCGUGUGUUUGACCUUUUUACAUCAUGGGUUCAGCCUCUUUGUAAUUAAACUGUUUGCUCUAUAUGUUAAGCCAUGUUCUAAGCCUUUAUUUGUUAAUUGUUUAUUAACCUUCCCCUUCAAGAGCUCACAGGCUAGUGGGAGGGAUAGAGGUCCAGAGAAGGGGAGUGUUUUCCUGUGAGGCCCACAGCCUAGCAGCAGUGUGGGCAGAGCAGUUGGGAUGGUGAUUGGGGGAGGUUUGUGAAGAUGCCACGCCUGGGUGGAAGGAAUGUUCUCAUGAAGAGAGGAGAGCGGGAGAAGGUCAGCAGGCUUGAGCUGGGAAGCAGAGGAAGUAAAGUGAGACAUCGUGGUCCUUUUGUGCUGUGCUGAGAAAUCUAAAUUUAUCCUGUCGAUCCCAAGGAACCAAAAUGGAUUUUGAAGGAGGCAGGGAACUGAGUGAGGCGUGAUCACAUUAUUUUACAGAGGACUCAGAGCUGCGUCUUUGGCUCAGGGCUCAUGUAAAUCCCUUUCCCCCUUUCCAGUUGAUUCUAUAGCAAACUCUCCUUUGAAUUUCUGUAGAACUUACUGCUCGUGUUCAUGACCAGUUCAUGAUGAAGCCUUUUCCUAACCUGGUUUCUUACCGCCUGCCUCAUGUUUUUGACUGUUUAUAGACGGAAGAAGCUAGAUGCGGUGGCUUAUGCCUAUAAUCCCAGCACUUUGAGAGGCCGAGGCAGGAGGAUUGUUUGAGCCCAGGAGUUCGAGACCAGCCUGGGCAACAUAGCAAGACCUCACCUUUACAAAAAAAUACAAAAAUUAACCAGGCAUGGUGGUGCGUGCCUGUGAUCCCAGCUACUGGGGAGGAUCACUGGAGCCUGGGAGGUGGAGGUUGCAGUGAGCCAAGAUUGUGCCACUGCACUCCAGCCUGGGCCACAGAGCAAAACUCUGUCUCAAAAAAAAAAAAAAAAGGAGGAGGAAGGAAGAAAAUUGCCGCUCAGGACAAUGGCAGCUGCUGAGUCGUGGUGCUGUGCAUGGAGGGUCUUUCCCAGAUAGUCUGUUCAUGUCUUUGCAGGCAAGUUUGAGGAUGACAUGAGAACCUUGAGGGAGAAGAGGACUGAGCCAGGCUGGAGCUUUUGUGAAUAUUUCAUGGUUCAGGAGGAGCUUGCCUUUGUUUUCGAGAUGCUGCAGCAGUUCGAGGACGCCCUGGUGCAGUACGACGAACUGGACGCCCUCUUCUCUCAGUAUGUGGUCAACUUCGGGGCCGGGGAUGGUGCCAACUGGCUGACUUUUUUCUGCCAGCCAGUGAAGAGCUGGAACGGAUUGAUCCUCCGAAAACCCAUAGAUAUGGAGAAGCGGGAAUCGAUCCAGAGGCGAGAAGCCACCCUGUUAGAUCUGCGCAGUUACCUGUUCUCUCGCCAGUGCACCUUGCUGCUCUUCCUGCAGAGGCCGUGGGAGGUGGCCCAGCGCGCCCUAGAGCUGCUGCACAACUGCGUGCAGGAACUGAAGCUCUUAGAAGUCUCUGUCCCACCUGGUGCUCUGGACUGCUGGGUGUUUCUGAGCUGUCUGGAGGUGUUGCAGAGGAUAGAAGGCUGCUGUGACCGGGCACAGAUCGACUCAAACAUUGCCCACACUGUGGGGCUAUGGAGCUAUGCCACAGAAAAGUUAAAGUCCUUGGGCUAUCUAUGUGGACUUGUGUCAGAGAAAGGACCUAACUCAGAAGAUCUCAACAGGACAGUUGACCUUUUGGCAGGUUUGGGAGCUGAGCGACCAGAAACAGCCAACACAGCUCAGAGUCCUUAUAAGAAACUGAAAGAAGCAUUAUCGUCAGUGGAAGCUUUUGAAAAACACUACUUAGAUUUGUCCCAUGCCACCAUUGAAAUGUAUACAAGCAUUGGGAGGAUUCGAUCUGCUAAGUUUGUUGGAAAAGAUCUGGCAGAGUUUUACAUGAGGAAAAAGGCUCCACAAAAGGCAGAAAUCUAUCUUCAAGGAGCACUGAAAAACUACCUGGCUGAGGGCUGGGCACUCCCCAUCACACACACAAGGAAGCAGCUGGCCGAAUGUCAAAAGCACCUUGGACAAAUUGAAAACUACCUGCAGACCAGCAGCCUCUUAGCCAGUGACCACCACCUCACUGAAGAGGAGCGCAAGCACUUCUGCCAGGAGAUACUUGACUUUGCCAGCCAGCCGUCAGACAGCCCAGGUCAUAAGAUAGUGCUACCCAUGCAUUCCUUUGCACAACUGCGAGAUCUCCAUUUUGAUCCCUCCAAUGCCGUGGUCCACGUGGGCGGCGUUUUGUGCGUUGAGAUAACCAUGUACAGCCAGAUGCCUGUGCCUGUUCACGUGGAGCAGAUUGUGGUCAAUGUCCACUUCAGCAUUGAGAAAAACAGCUACCGGAAGACUGCGGAGUGGCUUACCAAGCACAAGACGUCCAAUGGGAUCAUUAACUUUCCACCCGAGACCGCACCUUUCCCUGUAUCCCAAAACAGUUUGCCCGCGCUGGAGUUGUAUGAAAUGUUUGAGAGAAGCCCAUCUGAUAACUCCUUGAACACGACUGGGAUUAUCUGCAGAAACGUCCACAUGCUCCUGAGAAGGCAGGAGAGCAGCUCCUCUCUAGAGAUGCCCUCAGGGGUGGCUCUGGAGGAGGGUGCCCACGUGCUGAGGUGCAGCCACGUGACCCUGGAACCAGGGGCCAACCAGAUAACAUUCAGGACUCAGGCCAAGGAACCUGGAACGUAUACACUCAGGCAGCUGUGCGCCUCGGUGGGCUCCGUGUGGUUCGUCCUCCCUCACAUCUACCCCAUUGUGCAGUACGACGUGUACUCACAGGAGCCCCAGCUGCACGUGGAGCCGCUGGCUGAGGACUUCUGGGCCCAAAUGUGCAGGGAUUUCCCCCUGCCAGCAAGCAAGCAGUCGGUCCUGCAAUUCAGUUCUGACCCUGUCUACUGGAGCUGGCGUCAGACACCACAGGAUAGCCUUCUGGCAGGCAUUCCUCAGAGAGUCAAGUUCACUGUCACUACCGGCCAUUAUACGAUAAAGAAUGGAGACAGCCUGCAGCUUAGCAAUGCCGAAGCCAUGCUCAUCCUGUGCCAGGCGGAGAGCAGGGCUGUGGUCUACUCCAACACGAGAGAACAGUCUUCUGAGGCCGCGCUCCGGAUUCAGUCCUCCGACAAGGUCACGAGCAUCAGUCUGCCUGUUGCGCCUGCGUACCACGUGAUCGAAUUUGAACUGGAAGUUCUCUCUUUACCUUCAGCCCCAGCACUCGGAGGGGAGAGUGACAUGCUGGGGAUGGCAGAGCCCCACAGGAAGCAUAAGGACAAACAGAGAACUGGCCGCUGCAUGGUUACCACAGACCACAAAGUGUCGAUUGACUGCCCGUGGUCCAUCUACUCCACAGUCAUCGCACUGACCUUCAGCGUACCCUUCAGGACCACACACAGCCUCCUGUCCUCAGGAACACGGAAAUAUGUUCAAGUUUGUGUCCAGAAUUUGUCAGAACUUGACUUUCAGCUGUCAGAUAGUUAUCUUGUAGAUACCGGUGAUAGUACCGACCUGCAACUAGUACCACUGAACACGCAGUCCCAGCAGCCCAUCUACAGCAAGCAGUCGGUGUUCUUCGUCUGGGAACUCAAGUGGACAGAAGAGCCUCCCCCUUCUCUGCAUUGCCGGUUCUCUGUUGGAUUUUCCCCAGCUUCUGAGGAACAGCUGUCUAUCUCCUUAAAGCCGUAUACUUAUGAAUUUAAAGUGGAAAAUUUUUUUACAUUAUACAACGUGAAGGCUGAGAUCUUUCCCCCUUCGGGAAUGGAGUAUUGCAGAACAGGCUCCCUCUGCUCCCUGGAGGUUUUGAUCACGAGGCUCUCAGACCUCUUGGAGGUGGAUAAAGAUGAAGCACUGACUGAAUCUGAUGAGCAUUUUUCGACAAAGCUUAUGUAUGAAGUUGUCGACAACAGUAGCAACUGGGCAGUGUGUGGGAAAAGCUGCGGUGUCAUCUCCAUGCCAGUGGCUGCUCGGGCCACUCACAGGGUCCACAUGGAAGUGAUGCCGCUCUUCGCCGGGUAUCUCCCCCUGCCCGACGUCAGGCUGUUCAAGUACCUCCCCCAUCAUUCUGCACACUCCUCCCAACUGGACGCUGACAGCUGGAUAGAAAACGACAGCCUGUCAGUAGACAAGCACGGGGACGACCAGCCGGACAGCAGCAGCCUCAAGAGCAGGGGCAGCGUGCAUUCGGCCUGCAGCAGCGAGCACAAAGGCCUACCCAUGCCCCGGCUGCAGGCACUGCCGGCCGGCCAGGUCUUCAACUCCAGCUCGGGCACACAAGUCCUGGUCAUCCCCAGCCAAGAUGACCACGUCCUGGAAGUCAGUGUAACAUGACAACGCCAGGGUGAACACACGCCACUUCCCAGCUAGGAGUGCACUUUAUGGGACUGUGACUGGACUCUUCCGUUCUGGCUCCAGCCAGACCUUCAGUGGUCCUGCCUGGCCGUGGGGACAUCAGAGAGUGUCAUCACGCAGCUGGCCAGCUGAGUUCUGUUGUUGUUUUCAUGCCGCCUGUGAUCUCAGAUUCCUGCUUUUCUCACCCCGUCCCCAUGCUGGUGUCCGACGCCGCUUACUCAGAGCCCUGGCCUCCCUCCCCCUACCUCACACGCUGCUCAUGAAAGUUUCCACCCACGCUGUCUCCACGGAACAGCCUCCGUCUGCUGGCUCUUCGUGGAAGGCCAUUUGUCUUUCAGGUAGACACUCAGCAGCCCUCACGGUCUUAGUGACGUGUGUGCCUUUCUGGUCACACAGCUGCCCAGUUUCCUGAUCGGGGUGGAUUUGUGUCCCCUAAGGGGUAAAACAGCCGUUUACCGCAGAUCCUCUCAUUGUGCUUUUCUAGAAUAACACCCUUCUAGGGGAGGCGGGUGGGGGAGGGAGGGAUCAUAACCCCUUCUGUGCCUUGGGAUGCCGGAGCUGGGGGACCUGGAGGCCCAUCAGCCGGAGCCACGUGAAAGGUACUGAAGAAAGCUGAGACCCGGCUGUGAGGAGCGCCUCAGCGGUGAGGUGGUUUAGGGAUAAAUGUUUCUGGAACCCUGUGGUCCCCCAUAAUGUUGAUAGAAUAUCAUAUGCACUGGGAGUUAAAUAUAUUUAAUUUAAUGAUCAUUAUAUAUGUGGGGGUUAAUAUGUUGUUUUUCUGUCCCUUUAAAGUCUUUACAUGUAAUUGUAGCUGUAUAAUCGUUAUUUUUCUUUUGCAUCUUAAGUCUUAGAAAUUAAGAUAUUCCAUCGUGAGGAUGAGAGAGGUCCUCAGUGUGUUUUUGGUCUGGUUGUAGGGAAGGACUCAAGUCCUGGAAUGUCCUCCACUGGUCUACUGAGUUGCAGUCACACUGUUCCAAUGGAUUAUUUGCUUUCGGUUGUAAAUUUAAUUGUACAUAUGGUUGAUUUAUUAUUUUUAAAAAUACAGACUAACUGAUGUAAUGUUUAUGUAUAAGUUGCACCAAAAAUCAAGGACAAAAAUAAGUGUGUUUGUUUUUACAGGUGUGAAAGUCACAGCUUGUAAAUAAGUGUUGUAUGUAUUAAACCUUUUCCAGUUCUCCAAAGCGAUGUAUUUUUGUACACUUGAAAUAGAGUACUCUUAAUUUACUGGGCAAAUGUGCUUGGAAUUGAACUUGACAAGAUUAGCUCAAGCAGAUAGAGUCGGGUCCAGCAGUGGGUGGCCCUCGUGUGAAUCCCCGUGGAUGUGCAAGUUGUGGAGAGAAGGAGCACCGGGUUCCUGCCCAGCACUGUGCUUGCGGGAGGCGGUGGGGCAUGGGAGGAAGGAGGCACAGACCGGGGAAAUAUGACAGCCGUCAUUUCCAGUAUUCUCUGUGUUGUCUUUUAGCUCAUUCAAUAAAUAAAGGUGGUGUGAUUUUUUUUUCCUCCUGUCUUUUUCAUUUGUAGAAACUGGAGACGUGUAAAGAAGAUAAAUAAUUGUGUAAUUAAACUUUCCAGAAAUUUAUCUUCCUCAUGUGCAGUUUAACAAACUUGGUCAAACUAGUUAGCAAAUUAGAACUUCAGAAUCUAAUGAUAGUUUAGGGUUUCUAAAAUAAGGUUUUUUAUUGUAAAAAUUGACGAUUGCCCUGCAUUUCUACCAAGUCCUGUGAAUAAAGAGAUGGGAGAUUUGAUUCCGUCAGAAGAGACUGUAAUCCGUGUCGUCAGCCUGGGAGCCUUCCCCAGUGUAAUGUAGCUUUCUCUCUUACCUUCUGGAAGAGGGAAUGUUUCAUUUAUUACUGUUUGAUUUUCUUGUAUCUGGUUCUACUCCCAGGAUGAAAUUAUCCAACUACAUAUAUAUUUAGAGGAAGAAAGUGAAGGGGAAAUUUAAAAUGUUUACGGCGCUUAAUUGCCUGGAAAUGAAAUGAAAUCAAAUUUAUCAGUUUUUUUCCCCCUAAUUACCCAAAAGAUCUUUUGCAAACUAUGUUACAUGAAUGCUUCUGCCUCUUUAAGACAAAGAAGAAUGUCACCCAAAAUUGUCAUUUUUUUCUUAAUGUUCAUCAUAAAAGUCCUAAAAGAGUAACUGUAAUUGGAUGUUUAUUGUUUUUAUCUAAAGUAAGGUGUAUGUGUUUGAGACAAGCUGGUUUUGUUGAUAAAGAGAUGUUAAAUAAUUGUGAAGCCAGAUAUGCAAUGUGUAUCUGAAAAGCAAGGAAUUUGCAGCCGUUUUACAAAUAUCUGUGGAACAUGUAAAUACUGUCAAAUGGAAAAUAAAAUAAGUUAUAAUUUUUGUGAAUUUCAUGGGAUGUCCUAUGAUUGGAAAAAUUAUAACUCUUCUGAUUCUAAUGUGGAAAUUGUUGUAUUUAAUCUGAAAAUGACUUUACCUACAACAGUUCCAUUGUCAGCACAGCCUAGGAAGGUCAGAUCCUGUAUUAAUUACUCUUAGUGGAGAUGCCAGAUAUCCCAUACAGAAUUAGCAGAGAAAAUACACACAGGCUUCUAUUCAAAUUUUCUUUAGUGCUUAAAAUUAAGUUUUAAAAUGAAAUCAGACACUGCAGGUUUGUAUAUAAAAUGAAAAGCUAUACUACUUUUUACAAAAGGGCAAACUGGGCUGAUGUAAAUGUUUUACUUUCAACUGUGUUCUUUAAAAUAAAUCCUACCUGGUUUUUAAAUUUUAUUUUUCAUGAAAAUGCUCCUUUCUCUACAUUUAUUCAUCCUAUAUACAUCAGGCUGUAAGACCCCCCCCAGUCAUCAUUAAUACAAUGUGUUGGGAUUCUGUGACUGGAAAAGGUGACAAGUUGGUGACUUUGACACUGCAGGUAUUCCAUUUUCAUGGUUUACUAUGAAAAGUCAUUUUUCAUAUUAUGUAAUAUAUUGUUAGAUUAAAACCAUUGUAUUAAGACUUUAAAAUGUAAGCAUUGUAAUUCUGAAAAUACACAUUUUAAGAAGAAA